CUGCAGCCUCUCUGCCUCCGCAUCCUCGUGGGCCCUGACCUUCUCUCUGAGAGCCGGGCAGAGGCUCCGGAGCCAUGCAGGCCGAAGGCCGGGGCACAGGGGGUUCGACGGGCGAUGCUGAUGGCCCAGGAGGCCCUGGCAUUCCUGAUGGCCCAGGGGGCAAUGCUGGCGGCCCAGGAGAGGCGGGUGCCACGGGCGGCAGAGGUCCCCGGGGCGCAGGGGCAGCAAGGGCCUCGGGGCCGGGAGGAGGCGCCCCGCGGGGUCCGCAUGGCGGCGCGGCUUCAGGGCUGAAUGGAUGCUGCAGAUGCGGGGCCAGGGGGCCGGAGAGCCGCCUGCUUGAGUUCUACCUCGCCAUGCCUUUCGCGACACCCAUGGAAGCAGAGCUGGCCCGCAGGAGCCUGGCCCAGGAUGCCCCACCGCUUCCCGUGCCAGGGGUGCUUCUGAAGGAGUUCACUGUGUCCGGCAACAUACUGACUAUCCGACUGACUGCUGCAGACCACCGCCAACUGCAGCUCUCCAUCAGCUCCUGUCUCCAGCAGCUUUCCCUGUUGAUGUGGAUCACGCAGUGCUUUCUGCCCGUGUUUUUGGCUCAGCCUCCCUCAGGGCAGAGGCGCUAAGCCCAGCCUGGCGCCCCUUCCUAGGUCAUGCCUCCUCCCCUAGGGAAUGGUCCCAGCACGAGUGGCCAGUUCAUUGUGGGGGCCUGAUUGUUUGUCGCUGGAGGAGGACGGCUUACAUGUUUGUUUCUGUAGAAAAUAAAACUGAGCUACGA